AGUGCUCCCUCCAGCCUCCGCGCAUUUCAGCUGGCGCUGCAGCUGCUGCACAGAGACCCACAGAGGCCACCCUCGGAACCAGCGCCCAAUGAGAGGGCGGGACCUGUGUUCCUCCACACAAAGCCAGGCGCUGGGAUCUUUGAGAACCACCACCCCAGCCUUUACCCUUAACAUUCCAUCCGAGGCAAACCACACUGAGCAGCCGCCUGCAGGCCUGGGAGCAAGGCUACAGGAAGCAGGUGUUUCCAUCCCUCCCAGGCGAGGCCGCCCAACACCAACACUGGAGAAGAAGAAAAAACCUCAUUUGAUGGCGGAAGAUGAACCUUCAGGGGCCCUCUUGAAGCCGCUGGUUUUUCGCGUUGACGAGACCACCCCGGCUGUGGUGCAAAGCGUCCUCCUGGAGAGGGGGUGGAAUAAGUUUGAUAAGCAGGAGCAGAACGCGGAGGACUGGAACCUGUACUGGAGGACAUCCUCUUUCCGAAUGACCGAACACAACAGUGUUAAACCGUGGCAGCAGCUAAACCACCACCCUGGAACCACCAAGCUUACCAGGAAAGACUGUUUGGCCAAACACCUGAAGCACAUGAGGAGGAUGUAUGGCACUUCCCUGUACCAGUUCAUCCCCCUGACGUUCGUCAUGCCCAAUGACUAUACCAAGUUCGUGGCUGAAUACUUUCAGGAGAGGCAGAUGCUGGGCACCAAGCAUAGCUAUUGGAUUUGCAAGCCUGCUGAGUUAUCUCGUGGGAGGGGGAUACUAAUUUUCAGUGACUUUAAAGACUUCAUCUUUGAUGAUAUGUACAUAGUGCAGAAAUAUAUCUCCAAUCCUUUACUUAUUGGCAGAUAUAAAUGUGAUCUCCGCAUCUAUGUUUGUGUUACUGGCUUUAAGCCUUUGACCAUUUAUGUUUAUCAGGAAGGGUUGGUUCGGUUUGCCACGGAAAAGUUUGACCUCAGUAAUUUGCAAAACAAUUAUGCCCAUUUGACCAACAGCAGCAUCAAUAAAUCCGGGGCCUCUUAUGAGAAGAUCAAAGAAGUGAUUGGUCAUGGUUGUAAAUGGACGCUCAGCAGAUUUUUUUCCUACCUUCGUAGCUGGGAUGUGGACGAUCUGCUUUUGUGGAAGAAAAUCCACCGCAUGGUUAUUCUCACCAUUCUCGCCAUUGCACCAUCUGUCCCCUUUGCUGCCAAUUGCUUUGAGCUCUUUGGGUUUGAUAUUUUGAUUGAUGACAACUUGAAACCAUGGCUUUUAGAGGUCAACUACAGCCCAGCCUUGACCUUGGAUUGUUCAACAGAUGUGUUGGUGAAGAGAAAACUUGUCCAUGAUAUUAUUGACCUGAUUUACUUAAAUGGUCUAAGAAAUGAGGGGAGAGAAGCCAGUAAUGCCACACAUGGAAAUUCCAACAUCGACGCUGCAAAAAGUGACAGAGGUGGGCUUGAUGCUCCUGACUGUCUUCCUUAUGAUUCUCUUUCGUUCACAAGCAGAAUGUACAACGAGGAUGACUCUGUGGUGGAGAAAGCUGUGAGUGUGCGUCCUGAAGCUGCACCUGCCUCCCAGCUGGAAGGAGAGAUGAGUGGGCAGGAUUUUCAUCUGUCAACAAGGGAGAUGCCACAAAGCAAGCCCAAGUUACGGAGCAGGCACACGCCUCACAAGACACUCAUGCCCUACGCGUCCCUCUUCCAGUCGCACUCCUGCAAGACCAAGACCUCCCCGUGUGUCCUGUCAGACCGUGGCAAAGCUCCAGAUCCCCAAGCAGGCAACUUUGUUCUUGUUUUUCCUUUCAAUGAAGCAACUCUCGGAGCUUCCAGGAAUGGAUUAAAUGUCAAAAGAAUAAUCCAAGAGCUCCAGAAACUAAUGAAUAAGCAACAUUCCUAAGUGGUAAAAAAUCAAAUCAAGAAAAAGUGACAUGGAUUUUUAAAAACCAAGGAUCCUGUCCUAGAGAAAGCAAUAGUUCAAGUCCCUACCUGUGCCACCAGCAUGUUAACUAUGACAUUGGGACUGAAGAUGUGGCCAUAUGUAUAAAUAUAACAGCUCUGACAAAGCACAAUAUGUUCAAGUGGUGAUUAAACUACAUUACAUCCCAUGUUUAUUUGCUCAGGUGUCUUGAAAGAAUUCUACAAAUACCACACAGCCUCCCACCAGUAAUUGAAUGUGCUACACUACGAUUAUGCUAUGUAUGUAUUUAAAGAGGAGAAAAAGAUUAUUCUAAUAUUUUUAAAGGAUUAUUAGGUGAAAACAGUACAAAAGAAGCCAGGAGUUAACUUUCUGUGUGUUUUUUUUUAAAUCAACCAGUUAUUUGUUAAAAUUAUUUUGUUAACUUAAGAUCAGACAAUCAUUCAGAGUGAGAUAAAUCACUGAAAGCCCUAAUGACUCUGUUGUUUACAAAUCCUGGGCUUGAAAUCAGACUUUGCACCAAAGAGCUCCCUGUGGGGGCAUCUUUGGGCUGUAUUUAAAUAGUGGCCCCUUGGCCUUGUCACCAUUUGUUUACCAUCACAGCAUGUGAGGUCAUGGCCUCCCAGAUCAAAGUAUGCUGUCAUUCCUGCCACAUAAAAAGCAUCUGCAGUCCUAAGACAUAAAAAUUCCAGUAGGUUACUUGAAAACAUUAUUCUAGUGAAAGUAGUCAGAUACAAAAGGCCACAUGUUGUAUGACUCCGUUGAUAUGGAAUGUCAGAAUUGGCAAAUCCAUCAAAAGCAGAUUGGUGGCUUAGGGGAGGGGUAAUGAGGAGUGCCUACUGAUGGGUAGGGGGCUUCCCUUUGGGGUGACAGAAAUGUUCUGGAACUAUAUAGAGGUGAUGGUUGCACAACACGGGGAAUUCACUAAGUAUCACUCAUGGUACAUUUUGUGUUAUGUGUGUUUUACCACAAUAAAAAAGUUAAAAGCUGG